AGACUGUCCCGAGCUUCCCCCGGGCGGGCAGAGGGAAGCCGGCUGGGGAUGAGGAGUGGAGGAGGCAGGAAUGCCUGGGACACUCGCGGGGCAUGUGAGCAGGCCCAGAAGCCAUGGCCCACUAUAAGACUGAGCAGGACGACUGGCUGAUCAUCUACUUGAAGUAUUUACUCUUUGUCUUCAACUUCUUCUUCUGGGUCGGGGGAGCAGCCGUCCUGGCUGUGGGCAUCUGGACCCUGGUGGAGAAGAGUGGCUACCUCAGCGUCCUGGCCUCCAGCACCUUUGCCGCCUCCGCCUACAUCCUCAUCUUUGCGGGCGUACUUGUCAUGGUGACCGGCUUCCUGGGCUUCGGUGCCAUCCUCUGGGAGCGGAAGGGCUGCCUCUCCACGUAUUUCUGCCUGUUGCUCGUCAUCUUCCUGGUUGAGCUGGUGGCGGGAGUCCUGGCCCAUGUGUAUUACCAGAGGCUGAGUGAUGAACUGAAGCAGCACUUGAACCGGACUCUGGCUGAGAACUACGGGCAGCCCGGAGCCACGCAGAUCACCGCCUCAGUGGACCGACUCCAGCAGGAUUUCAAGUGCUGUGGAAGCAACAGCUCAGCCGACUGGCAGCACAGCACGUACAUCCUGUUGCGGGAGGCCGAGGGCCGCCAGGUGCCCGACAGCUGCUGCAAGACAGUGGUGGUGCGCUGCGGCCAGCGGGCCCACCCCUCCAACAUCUAUAAGGUGGAGGGAGGCUGCCUCACCAAGCUGGAGCAGUUCCUGGCCGACCACCUGCUGCUUAUGGGGGCAGUGGGCAUCGGGGUGGCCUGCCUGCAGAUCUGCGGGAUGGUUCUCACCUGCUGCUUGCACCAGAGGCUCCAGCGGCAUUUUUACUAAUGGCCAACCACCUCCUCUUCCAACUGCCCCUCAAGACAACAUGUGGCCACAUGCCAUCUGCAAGGCCUGCAGAGUUAGCACCAGCUCCACUAGGGCCAUAGAUGCCCCCUCCUUUGUGCCUAGCUCCUGCGAAUCCACCGAGUGCCUGAGACCAUAGCUUCUGUGCCCACCCAGGCAGAGACCCUCGGCCCCCUCUCCUCCAUUUCUGAGCCCCCAUGGCCAGAUCCUGGGCAGGGAAAUGAUCCUUUCAGGAGACAACCAGAGCCCCUCACCAGGAACGGGGGCACCCGUGGACUACGGGAGGGUGGCGGUUGGGUUCUCUGCUCCCUCCCAGCUCCUGAACCUGGAACAAUCGGCAGAAAACCCAGGAACCCCGGCACUCCUGCAUUCAGCACGGGAUUCCCCCACCCAUGCCCAGAAGCCCUGACCUUGCUGUUUCUGGAAAAAGCAUGGGGUGGGGCAGGGAGGGCUGGCAUUUCCCCCAGAAGACCUUGCCCUUUGACCUGCCCACUCUCCACACUGCCUCACCUGGAAAGCCAUGUCCUGCUGGCCUCAUUCCUUCCUGAAGGGCCUAGGAGUGGGGAGGCCUGGGUAGGGCAGCCACAGGCUGGGUAGAGCCGCCCUGGCAGGAAGCAGGGGGUAAGGUGGCCAUACCAGCACAUGCUGCACUAGGAGCAGAGCCCUGCACCUGCCUAGCUGCCUUCCUGGGAGAAACCUCCCUGGGAGACCAUGGCCCCAAGCCCUGGCCUCUAGUGAUACGCCCCUCGGGAAUCUCCUGUUCCGGGGCCUGAUUCUCAGGAACACCAGGUUUCAGACCAUCUUCAGCACCUAAUGUUGAUGGGUGUCAAACAUCUCCUGGAGUGGACCAACUCGCAACCCUGCAAAGUCGGAGCUGCUGAGAAGGGGCAGCUCUGAAUAGAGGGGCAUCUGCCUGAACCUCACUUUUCCUGGGGCCCUCUCCUUGACCCCGUAGCCACCACCACACUGCUUCCAGGGGGUCCAGCUCUGCUUCCCUUCCCACCUGUCCUAGAGUGGACAGAGCUUUUUCCUUGGGUUCUCUCUUGCAUCACUAAGUUCAGCAGGGAAUUUGCGGAAUUUUCAGGAAGAACUUUCCCCAGUAAUAAGGGAGAACAGAAAGAAAAUCCUAGAAAAUACAGAGUAUCCAUGCUGGCAGCUUUUUGUACAACACCCAUAGGGACCCCCCCAAAUGGCUAUUACAAAGGGGCAGCCCAUUCACUACACAAGAACCCCACACCUGGCUUCCACCCUCCCCAGCUCCUGCACUUCUCCCCAGAGCGGGACCCUCUUACUUCCCCCCAUGAAGGGGGGCACCUUGUGCUAAGGCCAAGGCUGAGCGAGGUCCCAGCUCACCUCCCUGCUUGAUCCAGAUUGCACUGUGAUGAGCACAUUGCUGACCUAGGCCAGUCCUGGGGCAGGCGUGCUCUCUCUCCCAUACAUAGGAGUGGCCUCAAGGCCACCCAGUGCUGACCCCAACAGAGCCCUGAACUGUCCAGAAACUGCAUCCUCAGCACAGGAAGUACCCACAUGGACAGAGGGAAGCCCAGCCUCGGGGCCGGUUGCCUCCUCUUCUCUGGGUGUUCUCCAGUGGCUUCUUGGAGCCUAGGCUGGUUUAUCUCCCCUGCCUAAAAGGCCCUGGGGUUGCCAAUGCAAAUUCAUUAAAACGAAGACCAGAUAUCCCAGACUGCACAGAGGCCGAGAGAAAUGGUAUAGUGCGUGAUUAGCAUUGCUGCCCUCCAACCUCCUGGGAUUCAUGCAGAUAAUCAAAAACUGACUAUGACUCCCAAGUUCUCUGAAGGAUGAGAUCACAACUGACAACUCUUACGACAGAGGGAGAGUGGUGAGAGAGAGAAAGAGGGUACUGGGCUAGAGCCAUGUUCUUCCUGCCGAGGUGCCAGGGGGAGGCGGCAGUGGGCAGGGGGUGCUGGGGCCUUACCUGUCUGCCCUGGUGGGGAUGAAAGACAGGUGACAGGCAGGUGCCCUGUGCACAGCCUUAUCAUUGAAGGCAGGCCCAGGACAGCCUGCCCCAUCUGCCCCAGCCCCAUGGGAUGGUUGGUCCAGCCUGACUGGGGCAGGAUUAGCUGCAAUUCCUGCCCUGUGUGUCGUCCAGCCAGACUGCCUCUUGAAAGAUGGCUUGUCCAAGCGGCAGACAGUGGUAGAACAACCCAGGGCUUGGAAAUCUGACCUCCUUGUCCAUGCCAACAGCCUGGGAGAUGAGACAGGGUUAGAGGAAACAGAGGCCCAGGAUACGGCAGGUUCUGCCUGGGAGUGUACAAUGGUUGGAGUCCAGAGCCAACGAUGUGGUCCCCAGCGGGGUGUGCCCCUCCUGCUGACGAGGGUACAGAUCCAUACCCAGGUCAAUUCCUCCCGGGCCCCUGUUUGGAGGCUGCUACAGCCUUGAGUUCCUUGGAGAGAGAGGACACGCCUGUGGAAUGUCACCUUCAGUCCCGUGCAGGCAAAAGGCCCCUGCACACCAGGGCCCUAGGAAAGCAGCAUCAGGUGCUGGGAUCCCACCCAGCUGGCACGGGCACGUUCUUGCCCUGCACACUCCAUGCUGCCCUUCCCUGAGCUCGCAGGGGCAGACACCAAGAGAAGGGCGCGUCCCCGAGUCCCCUGGGUGACCUGUGUCAGGACAGCAGGCAAGAAUGAAACGUGGCCUUGGCUGACGGGUUGGAAUAUUUGUGACCGUUCUUGUCUUUCUCCCUCCUGCUUCCCCGGCACCCUAGCCCCAUCUCCAGGAGCCCCUCAGGCAGAGUAAGUGGGGAGUGUGUCCAGGGAUUUUUUUGUGUUUACCAAGGUCCUGCUGUGCACUUAGAAUCUGUCACCAUAAAUACUUAUCUCGCAGUUACCCCAGCAAGAGGGUGUUAUUUCCCCCAUUUUAUAAAAGGAAAUUAAGGCUGGGCAAAGUUAAGACUUGCUUGUCAGUGGUCAUGGCUGUUGUCUUGCCACCCCCAGCUGGGGAGAAGGAAGAAAACUGGGCCGGGAACCCCUCCCCUCAGUGUCCCCCAGUUCUCCAUCUCCAUAAGGAGCCAUCAGGCUGUCAUUAAGGAACAGAGUGUCACUCAGGGGGCACUGUCACAAAGCAGCACCCAUGGCACAUGGGCCGGGGGUGCAGAAGCCUGGCUUAUUUCAGGCUGACAGCUGGACCCUCUGGGUGCAGGGGCUCAGGCAGUGGCCAAGAGCCCAAAGGGCUAAGGCCCGUGACGACCACCCAGCCCGUCACCCCAGGUACAAACACUGACCCCAAAGCAAGAGCAGGGACUGUCCCUCAGCCCUCAGGGCCUUCAUGCAGGGUGCAGAAUCUCAUGUCCACAUGGAGGUCACCCCUCAGGUCACACCCACUCCCAGAGCAACCCUGGGCAGGGAGGGGCACCCUGGGGUUGUGUUGACCACCUCCCCUUCAGGUGAGGCCCUUUUCUGCCUUCUUUCUAGCCCCCUGCAUGGGGCACCUGCUAUUGCUGGGGCUCUGGGGUGGACCCUGUGUGAUUUCUGUCAGGGAGCUUGUGCUGUGCAUGGCCAGAGGUGUUUACAUCCAGAAGGGCCCAGCACGGCCCUGUGGGGUGUGGGGGGAAUAUGGUAGAUCAUUGUGAUGUGCCUCGGGGCCCUCUUGCCUUGGAGCCAGCUUUGUUUCAGAAUCUGCUACUUGGGCCCUCUUCAGGGUUUUGAGGCUGGAGAAGUGAGUUGGGACAGUCACUGUCAUCACCACCCACCCUGUCACCCACCUGGAAAACAUUCUUGAUAUACUGGCCAUGCUGGGCCGGGCUCACAUCCACUGAGGGUAUAGUGACCAAGCGUCUAAACCAGUCGUUCUCAAACUUCGGUGAGUAUCAGAAUCACCUGGAAGGGCUUUUACAAACAGAUUGCUGGCCCCACCCCCCAGAAUUUCUCAUCAGGAGUGGGCAAGACCAAUCAUUUGCAUUUCUGACAAGUUCCCAGGAGCUGCAGCUGCUGGCCCUGGAACCACACUUUGAGAACCACUGCUUUAGACCAAACACCAAAGGAAGAUGCAGCCACCCUCCUUUACAUGUCACAACGCUCAGGGUCCAUGAGUACCUCAGGCUGUCCAGCUGAGCUCCACCUGCAGCAGCCGAGAUUCCCGACUCGCUCCACCAUUGGGGGCUAGGAGUGAAGCGUGUCACCAUGGUCAGCUCAUGGCCAGCCAGGAAAGCCUCUCUGCUGUGCGUCUGUGCAGUUCUUGUUCUUCCCUGGAGGACUCUUGGAUCGCCUGUGAUCUUGGCCAGGAGACCAGGUGCCUGGGUCCCUUCCUGGAAGGGGACAAGUUACACACCCCAGCCCCAUUUUCCCACCAACUUCUACAUGCCUUGGGAGAACCUGCUACAUGUUGGCUGCCCCCUUCCCCUAUUUCAGCAGUGCCCAGUCCUGCUUAUAAACCUGAGGCCUGCUCCCCAUACCCUGCCCUGUGCAAGUGCCAGCCGUUAUUCCAGGCAGCCCAAUGUUGUUGAGGCCAGAUGGAUUCCUGGAAGCAGCUGGCCCAUGGAUGUGAGUCAUCACAGUAUUCUAGAAACAGAGAAGAGGUCUUAACCUAAUGCGCAUAGAGAAAUUGUUCUCAUUGUAAACAUACCCCUGUCCUUAGCUGAUCUAGGUGGAAGCCCAGCUUCAUGUGCUAGGGGGCAUGAUAAUGAUAAUAAAGGAAUUGUAUCUAGGA